CUCCGGUGACCUAGGGUCAGCCCUGCCUUGGGAAGGGAGGUCGGGAAGUCCUAGUUCUAGGCACAGUGAGGCUGAGCUCAAAACAAGGAAGGCAACAAGGUGUCCACUGUGGCGCAGGCUCUGAGCUGUUUGGGACAGUUUUUAGGAUCUUGGAGUGUCAGAGUUCAAAGGGGCUUGUACAUCUCCAAACUCGGUGUUUUAAAACUGCUGCUGGCCAGGCCUUUCCAAGCCCAGUUAAGCCACAGCCUCUGGGUUCCUGACCCGGGUCUGGGGGUUGUCAGAGCUCCCCAGCUGAUCCUAACGUACACACUGGGGGUAGGAACAAGGGGCAAACUGAGGCUUGGGGCCAGGCGUGGGGCGGACACCGCGCUCACAGCAGGAAGCCUCCUCCGAUGGCCCCGAUGAGCCCUCCCCUCCAGCAGUCACUUCCCUGUCUCUGGGGGAAGUUCAGGGGCUGCAGAUCUGAGUGCCUUGUGGUUUCAGAGCAGAAGCCAAGCCUGCCUGUGGGCUCAGCAUCGCCGGCCCCAGGAAGAGCCAAGUCUGCACAGCGCCACUCUGUGGCAGACCGGGGUCCUGCACCUCUGAGCUAGAGAUUCCCCCCUUCCAACCCCUGGAGUCCCAAAUUCCCCUUGAGCCCCUGGAGCAGGUACUGUCUGUCCUCCCCUGCUCUGAAGGAGGCGGACUGGGGGGCCUUUGGGCUCGGAGCCCCGAGCUGAGGGGCAGGAGCUGGUGCCUCCCACUUUUCUGGAAGAGUGCGGAUAAGCUAGAGGGCUGGCUGCUACCUUUUCCCUGCCUCCAGGAGCUCGCAGGGGCUUGUGGAGUCGGCUAGCAGGGCCGGUUUUUCCUGGCCCCAUUUGAAGCCUUGGAAUUCCCAGCCUGGGUUACUCGAAGUCCAAGGAUCAAACCCUGGGAUCGGGCCAGGGUUGGAUGGGGACCCUCUCUGGGUAGCCUGUGAAUUGUCUCUGUUGUGGCAACAGCAGGGUCCUCUGAAACCACAGGGCUUCCCCUCCCUUUCCUGGUGUGCCGGGAGAGCUGUUUUUUUAACCUGCAGAGAUCCAUGUUGCAGGUGACAUUUCAGCUUGGUGGCUGUGCCGAAGCCUGGCCGCCUGGCUUUAAUUCCUCCCCCAGUGGAGUCUCAGAUCUCGGUGGCCUCACCGAGUGCGGUGUGGGACGCCGUGCUGCUGGCUUCACUUCCGCAUGCUGGCCUUUCUCCCCCGGCUGAGGCCACAGCCUGGGAGGUGACGUUUCGGAGUGUCGCUGUCAAUGAGAAUUUAUUGAGCUCCUCCUCUGAAUCCAGCCGUGUGCUUGCUGCUGGGAGGUGUACAGACAGAUAAAACAGGAGCGUGGCCAAAAGCAGCCCUUUGCAUGCCUGCCAAACGCACACUCGGGGGCCUUUUAAUCUUGCUUCUGCAGCUCUGAUUCCCCACCAGCCUCUUCUCUCACGCCCUCAGCUCCAGCCAGACGAAACCACACGCCAUUCUCGCCACUCCUGCGUUUGGCCACGUCCCUGUCCUAGCAUGGGCCAUCCCGUCUGCCUGGGAUUCUCCCGUCUGCUCCAAAGCCCACCUGUCACUGAGGCCAGUCCACCUGCCCCUCCUAACCUGAUGCCUCCCUCGCAUCCAUACUCCCAUGCCCACCCCGUGUCUGGAAUCAGAAGUUCAGAGGGGAAGUGAGAGCUGCCCCCGGGAGGCUGGGGCGGAGUCCAGGCCUGGAGGAAGGAGCUGUAGAUGAGGGCAGGGCUGGUGCUGGAGAGGGCCUCUGGUUUACCUUCACCUGCACCUACCAGUCAUCUGUGGAAAGAAGGGGUUGGGCUGCACUUGAGGCUUUUGUGGGUCCUUGUGACUUGGGGGUUUCUAGGGAGGCAGGUGGAGGAAGUGGGGAGCCUCCAGCUCGGGGGUCUCUCCUGGCUGCACUUUUGAAUCACCUGGGGAGCUUUAAAAGCUCCCAGUGUCCAGGCUGUACUGCCAGGCAGUUCAGGCCAAAUCUCGGAGGGAUGCAGCCUGGGCAUCCGUGUGUCAACCCUCCCCCCCCCCCCCCCGUUAACUGCCACGUGCAGCCCAAGCUGAGACCCUGGCUCUGCUUUCUUCCAGAGCAGCUUCCUAGUCACCUAGGGGCCAGGGUGGGAGCUUUUCAAUGCUUGGCCCCCCUAAUCCAGAAGGGCCUUCUGCUGGGGGGAGCAAUGUGGGUAGGAAUUCCUUCUCCUGGGAAGAUGGGCUGAUGCUGUUUCAGGAGACCUGGGGUCUCUCUUCCCACCUGGGAAGCCAGAGACCGCCUUGCUUGCCCCGGAAUUGGAUGGAGAACCCUGGUGACUCAGAAAUGGACGUCUCCCCUCUACGCCACCUCCCCCGCAGGACGGCGUGGCACCUGUCACCUGGCUGCUCUCUGGAUGUCUGUGGGCCUUGUGUUAACCCCAGGCAGAAUCCUGAAGGUCAUUCUUGCCUGGCCCAGGUGUGCUUUGAGCUCUUCUAAAGGGGCUUACAAAUGCAGAGUCCCACUGGCAUGGGUGGAUUCGUGUUCACCUGCAUCUCUAGCCAGGCCUUCCAAUUCUGGAACCGGUUCCUCCAGCUGGAGGACUUGACGUGUCUGAGGAGGUGUGUGUAAUAGUGGCUUUGGGAUCACUGGACUGAGGUGGCGUGAGGGGGGUGCGUGCUAAUGGUGACAUAGAUCCUUCCACUUUAAUCAUCACGUCCUCACCCCCACCCCCAUGUUCUCAUCUGUAAGACGAGGAUGCAGAGGCCCUCUGGCAGUUGAGGGUGAGGAUGAGAUGCUGUAAUGCCCGCCACAUGCCCCUGACGGGUAAAUGACAGAUGCGGGUGAGGGUUGAGAAGGCCUGGAGCGUGGGGUGAGCCCCUGAUGAGUGUCAGCUGUUACUGUGUCGAUCAGUGCAUCUGACUGUUCGUAUCUGCCUCUUGCUUAGCCUGUGUGACCUCAGGCACUUGUGUUCUGGGCCUCAGUCUUCUAAUCUGUGGAAUAGGAAUGACAAUGUCACCUGUAUCCUGAGGCUGUUGAGGGUUAAAGCCUUUAUUACCAAGUGCCCAGUACAGCACCUGACACAGGCUCUGCAAAGCCUUGCGGCUACUCCUGUUGCUGUUGUUUUAAUUAGAGACAGGGUCUUGCUCUGCUGCCUAGGCUGGGGCGCAGUGGUGCGAUCACAGCUCACCACAGCCUCAAACUCCUGCGCUCAAGUGAUCCUGCUGCCGCAGCCUCCUGAGAAGUUGGAACCACUGAUGCGUGCCGCGACACCUGGCUAAUUUUAAAGAAAUUUUUUUGUGGAGACAGGGUCUCUCACUGUGUUGCCCAGGGUGGUCUCAAACUCCUGAUCUUGGGUGAUCCUUCCGUCUCAGCCUCCCAAAGCACUGGAGUUACAGGCAUGAGCCACUGUGUCCAGCUUGGCUUUAAUUUAUAAAGUUCCAAGGCUCUGUUCCCCUACGCUCAACUGACUCCCUUGCGGUGUUGGGGGUGGCCCCUUUUCCCAAAAAGACUGGAGUUGCUUUUUCUGCCCUAAGGCUCAAGUCACCACAGCAGACCCUGCCGGCCCCUCUGCUGGGCUUUAACAACCGGAGGUUCUUUUUAGGAGCCUCAACGUCCCCUCGGGCUCACAUGCACACCACUGCCCCCUUGGUGAUUGGCACUCUGGGCCCAGGUGGCGGGAGAUGCUUUAACAAACUGUCCCUCCCCCAGCCCUGCCCUUCCUGCGCUCGGAUGGUGGGUCUGUGGCCACAGGCAGCAAUGAAGGGUAUCGACCGCCCAGCUUUUGGUUGAGCAGUAUUGAUGUUGGACAGGUUAAGCCGUCCCGAAGGAAAAUCUAUAUGUCAAGCUGAGCACAAGACAGCUUGCGAGUGGAGGCGGGAGGGGGGUGGGGCGCAGCCUUAAGGGCCACUUCUAGGCUAACCCUGAGUCUUAUCUUCUGGGUUGGGGGGCAAAGCCCGGGGGUGCCAAGCGAUGCCCCACAGCCCCAGACGGGCCUGGAGGGACGGCAGGCGCUCUUACGUGGUGUGAUCUGUGGGCAGAUGGUGUGCCGGCCAGGUCUUGAUCCCACUUAAGGAGUUGUCUCUGGGAUUUAGUAACCAGAUGGGAAAGACUGUAUUUCUGUAUCCAGAGGUGCUGUGGCUGCCCCAGCCUAUGAGGGUCACGCCGUGGGCUGUGCGUCAGGCGUGGUGGGGGGACGUUUUCACCCCAACGUGCUCCUCCUCCCCAGGGAGGGACUGACUUGCUAGGCAGGGAUUAUCCCCAUUUAGCCAUGCACCAGGGAAGAAAGGGGCCCCGGGGAUCCAUAUCCUCCCUGUAGUCACACAGCUGGUAAUUAAUUGGUAGAGGAGCAGAAACCCACACCAUGAUUUUCCCACUCCAGCCUCCUCACCCAACUCCCACCCGCUCUCCCUUAGAGCCUGGAGAGAGGUCACCGGCUGCUUCGGAAGGCCCUGUUUAACCUGGGCUGCUUAUGGGGUGCGGUGGCUCAAGCCUGUAAUCCCAGCACUCCAGGAGGCCGAGGCAGGUGGAUUGCUUGAGCUCUGCAGUUUAAGACCUCCUCUCUACAAAAAAUAAAAAUAAAAAUAAAAAGAACUGGCCAGGCUUGGUGGGAUGCGCCUGUGGUUCCAGCUACUCAGGAGGCUGGGCAGGGAGGAUCACUUGAGCCCCGGAGCUCGAGGCUGCCUGCAAUGAGCUGUGAUCGCACCACUGCACCCCAGCCUGGGUGAUAGAGCGGGACUCUUGUCUCAGCAAAAAAACAAAAUUAAACUGAGCUGCUUCACCCAGUCUCGGGAUGUGAGUGGAUUCUUCCAACUGAAUUCCCAGUGUACAUUUAUCUUUGAGUGUAUUUUUGUAAUGUUUUUGCAUUUGACAUGUGGUAUUUUUUCCAUUCACUUAAAUAUACGAGGAUCCACUAGACAGCCGAUGCUAUACUGGGUGUUGAAGACACAAAGUGGAAUGCGGUUCAAGCAAAAAUUCUCAGCCAGAUGGGAGCAUUGGAGAGACUUCCGCCUCCCAGAGGCUGCCGAUCCACGCGGUCGUCUCUGCCGCCCGUCGGGAGGGUGCGGUUAGUCACCCCGUAACAGAUAAGAAAACAGGGUUUCGGAAUCAGCCCUUGUGGAAUGCCUGGGCUGGCGCCCCACUCAGCCCUGCAUCUCUGAGCUGUUGGGGAACCCGUUUAGAUGGUCUCAGCCUUGGGUCUCUGCACUGUUCUCAGCCCUGGGUCUCUGCUCUGUUGAGGAACCCGUUUAGAGGGUCUCAGCCCUGGGUCUCUGCUGUGUUGGGGAAGCCGUGUAGAUGGUCUUGGCCAUGGGUGUCUGCUGUGUUGGGGAACCCGUUUAGAGGGUCUCGGCCCUGGGUCUCUGCUCUGUUGGGGAAGCCGUGUAGAUGGUCUCGGCCAUGGGUGUCUGCUGUGUUGGGGAACCCGUGUAGAUGGUCUCGGCCCGGGGUCUCUGCUGUGUUGGGGAAUCCGUUUAGAUGGUCUCAGCCCUGGGUCUCUGCUGUGUGGGGGAACCCAUUUAGAUGGUUUCAGCCCUGGAUCUCUGCACUGUUGGGGAACCCGUGUAGAUGGUCUUGGCCCUGGGUCUCUGCCCUGUUGGGGAACCCGUUUAGAUGGUCUCGGCCCUGGAUCUCUGCACUGUUGGGGAACCCGUGUAGAUGGUCUUGGCCCUGGGUCUCUGCUGUGUUGGGGAACCCGUUUAGAUGGUUUCGGCCCUGGGUCUGUGCUCUGUUGGGGAACCCGUUUAGAUGGUCUUGGCCUUGGGUCUCUGCGGUGUUGGGGGAACCCGCUUAGAUCGUCUCUUGAAAAAGGUUUGUGUCCACCGCCCCCCGUGCUGGGGUGUGCAGGGAGUGGAGUGUGCGCUGAGAUCGUAUCUAUUUUAAAUCAAGCCGAUGUCCUGGCGUCCUUUUUUGAAUACAGUCUUAUCGUUUUACAACGUGUUGUUUCCACCUAAAUGUACAUCUUAUAAGACUUUAUAGGACUAAGGAAGUUAAUCCAUCCUUAGCAGGGAUGCCAGACCCCUGGAGCCUGUCACCUGGGCACAGGGAGGACAUUUUAACUAAGCAGCUGGUUUCCAGGUUGAGACUGGUUGGGAUCCUGCGGAGUGACUCUGAAUCCACUAACAGCAGGACUGUGUCUGCUUGGAUGCUGGAGCUGGGGUUUCUCCAGCCACGGCUGGCAGAGUGGACCCUGGGGUUUUGUGUCAUCCGUGUCUCUUAUCCACUGGAGAGACUGUUGUGUUCCUUCUGCCAGAUUACCCUUGAAGAAGCAGGGGAGGGGAGGGCGCUCCGGCCCACCUCUGCUUACCUGCCCACCUCGGGCUCAUUCUUCCCACCCCAUACUCCCCAUGCAGCCUUCAGGACAGGAGACAUAGCCUGGACUACUUCUCAUGGCGCAACAAGAACUUUGUUACCAGUCUUGGUGGCAGAGACUGCCAGCUCCCAACAGCCAGGUCUGCACCUGACUGGGAAAUUUACUAGUUCCUCACUGGGAUUCUGGAGGGGCGUGUGUGUGUGCAUGUUGAGAAUUACAGAAUCAUUUAGACUUAAGCAGUCAGCCAUUCAGCAGUUGACAGGAUGAUUGUGGCCGGAAAAGGUGACCAGUUUGUCCUGUUUGGUGGCUGGGUUGGAUGAGGGAGUCCAGGACUCCUGGCGCAUGACUGUUAUGGGAGCUUUUCCUGGACAGCUCCAUUCCAAAGUCCAUCUUGGCUGAGGGUGCUUGUUGGUUUUUUCCAGUGAGGCAUUUAGUGAUGUCUGGGCACAGCACUUGGGGCUUUGAAGAUGGGAGACGAGUCUGGACGAGGAAACGCCAUUAGAACGUGGAUGGUUCUGGGCCCUUUCUUUUUCCACCCUGUAUUUCCUCUGUCCAGGCAGGUCAUAUUGGGGAGGGUGUUCAUACUCGUGGGUUGCCACUUAGGGAACUCUGUGCUGUAGGAGUUUGUAGCCUGGGUUCAUGGAUGCUACACAUCUUCAAACACACGCUCCCACAGGGUUUACAGAUAGGCUCUUCGAACUUGGUAAAACUGUAUGUAACAUGCAGUAGGUGUAUUUUCCUGGGGAGAGGGUCUGGUCCGCCACUUUGAACCAUCUUGAGAGUGGACCUUUUUGCAAAGGCGGAUGUAACUGUUUUAUGACUUGAGGGGCAAGUCCUGACUUGGUGAGCUUGCUUUGAUUCAGGGGAGACCUACCUUGGGGUUGACACACGCCAGAAUUGUGGCCUUCAUAGGCGUCCCCUGAAGCUGAGCCUGGGAAGGGGUUGACCUCUUUCUGUUACACCCUCAUGGAGUUACCGUGUCGAUGACAUCUGAGUGGAGUGUCUGUGCUGAGGGUUGCAGCUGCAGCUGCCGCAGGGCUGUUAGUUGCUCAGACCUGCAUGUACUUGGAGAAUUGGGAAGACCUGGUGUUGAGGAAGCUGGCUGGCCUGAGACCAUAGGGAGGGGAGGGGUGCAGACUCUGGCAACCUGGAGAGUUAGGGACAAACUAAGGGAGAAGUGCCACUCAUGGGGCUGUGGUUUUUAUGGCUUAGACUUUUCGGGAGAAACUGGGCACCUUCUCGUUGACUUGAAGCCUCCUAUUUUAAGACAUUGCCCAUUGAUUCUCGUUUAAACAACACAGCGUGAUUUCAGGUCAAAUAAAAACAGGUUGAAGGGUAAAAGGCUGGCCCCUUGUCCACUCCUUUUUUUUUUUUUUUUUGAGACAGGGUCUCGCUCUGUCACCUACAUUGCAGUGCAGUCGCGCAAUCACAACUCAAGGCAGCCUCAACCUCCUGGGCUCAAGCGAUCCCCCACCUCGGCCUCCCAAAGCGCUGGGAUUAUAGGCGUGAGCCACUGUUCACUGACCCUCUUGUCCAAUCAUUUGCACCCUCUCUCCAUGGUACUGACAGGGAAACUGAGGCUCAGGCCAUGCGGUGCCCUGGAAGUCCGCACUGAGCUGUUGGGCAUGAGUCAGCCUGGGCCCACCCCCGUUCCCCUUGGUUUUCCAGCUCAGGACCAAGCCCUUUUUGCUCUGCCCCCAUAGUGUGUUCCCUCGAGGCCCCACAGCUCUCAGCCUUCAGUGGAAGUUCAGGCUGGCUGAGUGGGAUGUGAGGACCCCGGUGCCUGCAGGCAGGCACACUGCGCCUUCUGACUUAAAGGCGCCCAUUUCUGCUGGUGUGGGCGUCCGCCCUGUUGGAGGGAAGGGACGUUUUCCAGUCAUCACCAUCUCCCCGCCUCUGAAGCUGGAGACCCUGGACCCCUCUUCGAAGGCCAGGUGGCCCUUUCUGCCCCCGCGCCACCUCCCCUGCUGCCCAGGCCACUCCUGGCCCCUGUAUGAUUGCUUCUUUGAGCACCUGUUGGUGUCCAGCUCCUGUACGGCCUGGUCCCUGUUCUUGGCUGUAGACUAAGGGCCCUGUAGAUAGGUACUGGCACUCACUCGGUACAGAAGGGACAGGCAUUCAUAGGAGACGUCCUUGGAUCCUCUCUCCCUCCCACUUACCUGAGGGAGCUUGUUAAACACUCAGCCUCCUCCACACUGGGGAGAGGAGAGGGGCCUGCAUUUCGUGGGUCCUUGUGAGCAAGCGUCUCAGCCUCCUCUUCCUGCUGGCCCAUGCCCCCCGGCCGCCACCCGCCGUCCCACGGAAACUUGGAGACCUCAGUGCCCGCCCUGGGGUGGGGGAGCCAGGUUGGAUUUCCCUCCUGGGCACCUCUCACCUGCCUGGACACCUUGGACCUCAUCCGUUCCUCUGCCCAGGGCCUCUGGAGGGAGGAAGGGCUCCCACAGGAGCAGGUGCAAUGGAAGGCAGCCUGGUCAGCUCUGGUGCCAUGGGCUACACAGGGCACCCGGGGGCGGUUCCGGCCUCUAGCACAGGUGCCCUCUGGCUGAGAGCUGUGGGAAAGUGGGGCUGGGGGAGGCCUCGAGUCCAGAGCCUUCCUAUUCCCAGCCGUGUAGGUCCCGUCCGUAAAACGGGUAUAGCACUAGGGUGGGCACCCAAACAGCCGCCACAGGGUGAGAGCUGCCACAGGGAGGGGACCCCAAGUGACGCCAGCCAUUUCCAAUCUCUUCGCACAUUAAAGGGAAGCAGCCGGCACCAUGGCCAGGACAGCUGGGUUUCCUUCCGGCUCCUGAGCCUCUACAUGUGACCCGGGUUGAGGGCGUGAAUCUCCAGCCUCCGUUCAGCCUCUGUAGGCUGGGAGUGAGCAUCCCACUGUGUGGAAUAAACAGGUGGAGAGAGGCGCCUGGGCACCGCCAGGACCACUGCCUCCGGGAAGCAGCCCAUGGGGAGAAUGUGACAAGGGACCCCAGGUACCGCCAAGGGCACAGGGUGGCGGAGGGGCUGGGAAUCGGCCGGCAUGGGUGAGCCCCCGGCUCUGUCUCAGCUGAGCUGUGUGGCCCCAGCGGCCUGUGUCACUUUGCUGUUCGCAGCUUUGCUUUCUGGGGUCUGCUUACGUAAAGGGAAGUAAGGGUACAGGUAGCCGGCGCCCUGUAAAAGUUGCCCCCUGGUACCUUGAUCGCUGUUGGUGCUGGGCACCAUCUCCCAGAGUCACAGCUCUGGACACCGACCCCAGCCUUGACUCAGGGCCCCGCCCUCUCCCUUGGUCUGUCGUGCCCCUUUAGGAGGCCGCCUCCCUGCCGAGGCCAGGCUGCCGCCCGCAUCUGCCAGUCCCGCCCUUCCCGCCGCCCUCCUCUCCAGCCCUUCAUCUGCCCGGCCUGCUUCUCCGCACACACAGCAGCCGCUUAGGAUAAUCGCGUCAAAUGUUGCUGCCAUCUGUUGCCUGACUUCCCGUCCCUCGCCUCCAUCCGGGAACCUCCGGGACCAGUCCGUGGCCGUGAACCUCAGUCGCAGGACCGUCGGCUCCUAGGAGGCUGCUGUCCGCGGGUCCCCAGAAUGCAACCUCAGCAUCCAGCGCCUUCUGUGCAGAGCCCCCCUGCUGUCCUCAAAACUGUAGUGUGGCGUCCAACCUGGGAAGCCCCUCCAGGCAUGAGCCAUGAGCCCAAGUCCCCUUCGCUAGGGAUGCUUUCCACCGCGACCAGGACCACCGCCACCGUCAACCCCCUCACCCCCUCGCCGCUCAAUGGCGCCCUGGUGCCCAGCGGCAGCCCCGCCACCAGCAGCGCGCUGUCGGCCCAGGCCGCGCCAUCCUCCAGCUUUGCCGCCGCGCUGCGCAAGCUCGCCAAACAGGCGGAGGAGCCCAGAGGGUCCUCACUGAGCAGCGAGUCGUCCCCCGUGUCCUCUCCGGCCACCAACCACAGCUCCCCCGCCAGCACACCCAAGCGCGUGCCCAUGGGCCCUAUCAUCGUCCCCCCUGGGGGCCACAGCGUGCCCAGCACCCCCCCCGUGGUGACCAUCGCUCCAACCAAAACCGUGAAUGGUGUCUGGAGGAGUGAGAGCCGGCAGGAUGCCGGCUCCAGGAGCAGCAGUGGAGGUCGGGAACGCCUCAUUGUGGAGCCCCCGCUCCCUCAGGAGAAGGCAGGGGGACCAGCCAUCCCCUCGCACCUGCUCAGCACCCCCUACCCCUUCGGCCUCUCCCCCAGCUCAGUUGUGCAGGAUUCCCGCUUCCCGCCACUCAACCUCCAGCGGCCCGUGCACCACGUGGUGCCCCCCAGUACCGUGACCGAGGACUACCUGAGAAGCUUCCGGCCCUACCACACCACCGACGACCUCCGCAUGUCCUCACUGCCUCCCCUCGGCCUGGACCCGGCCACUGCUGCAGCCUACUACCACCCCAGCUACCUGGCCCCACACCCCUUCCCCCACCCGGCCUUCAGGAUGGACGACUCCUACUGCCUGUCUGCCCUGAGGUCCCCGUUCUACCCCAUCCCCACCCCCGGCUCCCUGCCCCCACUGCACCCAUCAGCGAUGCACCUGCACCUCUCUGGGGUCCGCUACCCUCCCGAGCUCUCCCACUCAUCCCUGGCAGCGCUGCACUCGGAGCGCAUGUCUGGCCUCAGCGCGGAGAGGCUGCAGAUGGACGAGGAGCUAAGGCGGGAGAGGGAGCGCGAGCGCGAGCGCGAGCGUGAGCGUGAGGCUGACCGCGAGCGGGAGAAGGAACGUGAGCGCGAACGCGAGAAGGAGCGCGAGCAAGAGAAGGAGCGUGAGCGUGAGAAGGAGCGCGAGCGCGAGCUGGAGCGCCAGCGGGAGCAGCGGGCCCGGGAGAAGGAGCUGCUGGCCGCCAAGGCCCUGGAGCCCAGCUUCCUGCCCGUGGCCGAGCUGCAUGGGCUGCGUGGCCAUGCCACUGAGGAGCGGGGCAAGCCCUCGGAGCAGCUGACCCCAACCCGAGCAGAGAAGCUGAAGGAUGCCGGCCUGCAGGCGCCCAAGCCCGUCCAACACCCCUUGCAUCCGGUGCCCACCCCACACCACACGGUGCCCAGCCUCAUCUCCAACCAUGGCAUCUUCUCUCUGCCUAGCAGCAGUGCUGCCACAGCCCUGCUGAUCCAGCGCACCAAUGAGGAGGAGAAGUGGCUGGCGCGGCAGCGGCGGCUGCGGCAGGAGAAGGAGGACCGGCAGUCUCAGGUGUCCGAGUUCCGGCAGCAGGUGCUGGAGCAGCACCUGGAUAUGGGCCGGCCCCCGGUGCCGGCGGAGGCAGAGCACAGGCCGGAGAGCACCACCAGGCCAGGACCAAACCGUCACGAGCCAGGUGGCCGUGACCCUCCGCAGCACUUUGGGGGGCCACCACCUCUGAUUUCGCCCAAGCCCCAGCUCCAUGCUGCACCCACGGCCCUCUGGAACCCCGUGUCCCUGAUGGACAACACCUUGGAGACGCGGCGGGCCGAAAGCCACUCUCUGCACAGCCACCCGGCUGCAUUUGAGCCCAGCCGCCAGGCAGCCGUGCCGCUGGUGAAGGUGGAGCGGGUCUUCUGCCCGGAGAAAGCAGAGGAGGGGCCACGGAAGCGUGAGCCUGCCCCUCUGGACAAGUACCAGCCACCUCCGCCGCCACCACGAGAGGGAGGGAGCCUGGAGCACCAGCCCUUCCUGCCCGGGCCCGGGCCCUUCCUGGCUGAGCUCGAGAAGUCCACCCAGACCAUCCUGGGCCAGCAGCGGGCCUCCCUCCCACAGGCGGCCACCUUCGGGGAGCUCAGCGGACCCCUGAAGCCUGGCUCGCCCUACCGGCCCCCAGUGCCACGGGCCCCCGACCCUGCCUACAUCUAUGAUGAGUUCCUGCAGCAGCGCCGGAGGCUGGUCAGCAAGCUGGACCUGGAGGAGCGCAGGCGGCGGGAGGCCCAGGAGAAAGGGUACUACUACGACCUCGAUGACUCUUACGACGAGAGCGAUGAGGAGGAGGUCAGGGCCCACCUCCGUUGCGUGGCCGAGCAGCCGCCCCUCAAACUGGACACGUCCUCUGAGAAGCUAGAGUUUUUGCAACUUUUUGGCUUGACCACCCAACAGCAGAAGGAGGAAUUGGUGGCCCAGAAGCGGAGGAAGCGGCGGAGGAUGCUGCGAGAGAGAAGCCCGUCGCCCCCAACAAUUCAGAGCAAGCGGCAGACGCCUUCACCGAGACUGGCGCUGUCUACCCGCUACAGCCCUGAUGAGAUGAACAACAGUCCCAACUUCGAAGAAAAGAAGAAGUUCCUGACCAUCUUCAACCUGACCCACAUCAGCGCUGAGAAGAGGAAAGACAAAGAGAGACUUGUUGAAAUGCUCCGUGCCAUGAAGCAGAAGGCACUGUCAGCAGCAGUGGCCGACUCCUUGACAAACUCUCCGAGGGACAGUCCUGCCGUCUCCCUGAGUGAACCAGCCACGCAGCAAGCCUCUCUGGAUGUGGAGAAGCCGGUUGGUGUUGCUGCUUCCUUGUCUGACAUCCCAAAGGCCGCGGAGCCUGGGAAGCUGGAACAGGUCCGGCCCCAGGAGCUGUCGAGAGUCCAGGAGCUAGCUCCUGCCAGCGGGGAGAAGGCCAGGCUGAGCGAGGCCCCUGGAGGCAAAAAGAGUCUGAGCAUGCUUCACUAUAUCCGGGGCGCUGCACCCAAGGACAUUCCUGUGCCGCUGUCCCACAGCACCAAUGGGAAGAGCAAGCCGUGGGAGCCCUUUGUGGCAGAAGAGUUUGCACAUCAGUUCCACGAGUCAGUGCUGCAGUCCACCCAGAAGGCCCUGCAGAAGCAUAAAGGGAGCGUGGCUGUGCUGUCUGCAGAGCAGAACCACAAGGUUGACACGUCCGUCCACUACAACAUUCCUGAGCUGCAGUCCUCCAGCCGCGCCCCUCCACCCCAGCACAAUGGGCAGCAGGAGCCCCCCACUGCAAGGAAGGGCCCCCCAACCCAGGAGUUGGACCGGGACUCGGAGGAGGAGGAAGAGGAGGAUGAUGAAGAUGGAGAAGAUGAGGAGGAAGUCCCCAAGCGCAAGUGGCAAGGGAUCGAGGCCGUUUUUGAAGCUUACCAGGAACACAUAGAAGAGCAAAAUCUGGAGCGGCAGGUGUUACAGACACAAUGUAGACGACUGGAGGCCCGGCACUACAGCCUCAGCCUGACGGCAGAGCAGCUCUCCCACAGCGUGGCGGAGUUGAGGAGCCAGAAACAGAAGAUGGUCUCAGAAAGGGAGCGGCUCCAGGCAGAACUGGACCACUUACGAAAGUGCCUUGCCUUGCCUGCAAUGCACUGGCCUAGGGGCUACCUGAAGGGAUAUCCCAGGUGACGGUUUCCCUUGCACUAGGCCGAACCUAUAGUAUAGAAAUAUUAUCUAUUUUAUUACCUUGAAUAUUUAAUAUUUUUCACUGGGAGGUUUGAAGCUUACAAAAUGAGAAUGUGCCAUGCAUGAAGCAAAGGAUUCCAGGCUCCAGAAAAAAUGAAUGAACUCACCUUGACGUCAAUGCAAUUGAAUCACCGUUGUCAUUCAGCGAGCAACCAAUGUAGGAUUGCCCACAGUUUUUCUUUUUAAAGGUGGUUUUCGCCCUUCCUCUCCCACAUUAUUUCUUAAUCUGAACAUGAAGGCUCCAUUAGCAACACUAAAACUUGAUCAUUAACAGCCCCCUGUGCAUAUGAGUGGAUCAAACCGGUUCUGUUCUUUCUUGUGUUGCCAUGUUACUAUGCCUCAAGCCCAGUUUGCUUUUGCCGCAGCGAUGGGGCCAGUCUCAUUCCUCCCCAGGAGUGAAACUUGCUUCAGCUGAAAAGGUUGGGUGCAUUGUCAGUAAAAAGGGCUUAUUUGUUUCAUUUUACUUUCCUGCAAAAUUUUCUUCAAAGCAACAAGUCCUAGGAGCACACAAAGCAACCCAAAGGCUUUUCCCUGGAAAAGCUCUUUCUUACCUAAAGAUAAAACCAAUUCACAAACUGAAGGUAGCUUUUUAUUACUCCGUGGGGAGCAUGUACAGAGCUCUGUGUAUACACAGCUUCACACCCACCAGAUUGUUACUACAGUGGGUUGGGUUUUCAUACAGACGUAAAUUUUGAGAGAAAAGUCAAAGGUGCUUCAGCCUUGUACUGUGUAUAUAUAUUAAAAAAAAAACAAAGUUUUGUAUGUUUUUAUUACUUUAACUAUUGUUAUAAAAAGCCUGCCAUUUUUAAUAUGUGGUUUGGGGGAUUUUUGUUUGUUUUUCCUGUUUGGGGGUUUUGUUUGUUGUUUUGGUUUUUUUUGGGCAAAAAAAAAAAAAAAACCUUGCUUUUAGUGUUUGUACUGCUGCUGGUCAGGACAUUAAAAUAUUGAAGUGUUUUUAAAAAUUAAAGAAGAAGAAAAGUAAAAGAGCUUACCACUGGCGCCUAUGCGAUCACUUCAUUUUUAGUUUGAGUUGCACCAGAAGCUGCCGUAGAAAGCCAUGCGCUACUGCUUACCUCCUCCACUCCCCCUGCCUGCCCCCAGCAUCUGGACAAGCUAAUAGCAAAUAUUACCCAUUGCUAUCAAGGGAGGAGGGGGUAGUCUGUAGAACCCAUGUGUGACAGUCAUGUGCACACAUGGGCGGGGGCUUUUAAAAACCUUUCAGGAAGUCAAUGAUUUCUGUGAUUGAUAUAAUUCUAAGGUGUCUGAGAGCAGGUACAGAAUAGGAACUUCAGAGGCUUUGUUUAAACGCAAAGCUUUGUAAAAGCCACAAGGUCUGAGCUGAACCCCUCCUUUUUGAACUUACUGUGACAAGCACAGGAACGGUCAGAAACUGGGCUCAUCACACCAAGGCAAAGCAACGGGCGAGUCUUCCUCCUUGUCCUAGUUACUGCCUAUGGAGGCAGUGUUUAGAUCAAGAAGGCCUCUCUUGCUCCCAAGGGCCCUCACCAGAGGCCAGGGCUGCCAGUCACUGGUCUGGGGGGUGGAGGCCUGAGCUGAGGGCAGGGUGCCUGACCUGUGUGCCGGCUGCUCACUGCUGUGACCAGCAGCCGAGCCCUUGGCCCUAGCCCUUGCUGCGCAGAACAGCUUGCUGGCAGCUGGCAUCGUGUCGCUUUAUCUGCCCCCGCACAGUUUGCUUUGUACGUCUGCCAAGAAUCUUCCAGUUAUUAGCAAACUCAGACGAAUGUACCGCCAGUAUUAUCAGCAGUCAACAAGCACCUUCCUCUCCACAGAAGCAGCUGGAAGAGAACUCGAGGGGCUGUGCUGCAGGCCUCCCCUCGAAAGACACUGGGAGGUCAGCAUGUUCCACAGGUGUUCAGAGGGAGUCUGCUACAAACUAUCAGGGCAAAAUCUCACUGGAUUUCUCCACUGAAAACCUACUUGAGGUUUCUGGUCUGAAGGCUUAAGAGUCACAUCUUAGCACUUCCGCUCUCAGGCCUCCUCCUCCAUCACAGAUGUCUGGAUGCUUUUGGAAAUGGCCUUGGCUAAAGUAAAAGGGAAAAGUAGAUCCGAUAACUUAAAAACGUAGCUCAUCCCUUACCAUCCAAGGGGCACUCCCUUGGUUGGAUUUUCUAUGACAGCACAGGGGACAGGUGGCACACCAUGAGAGGUCUGCCCAGGGUGGGAGCAGUGUCACUGUGCUAGCAAUAGUUGGCUUCUCCCCUGUCAGUGGAAACCCCACUUCUGCCCGGCCCUUGAGCUUCUUGCCCACUGUCUCCCCAUCCUUCCACCUACUUGUGGCGAUCUGAGUACUCUACUCUUGCUCAAGAAGUAAUACGACAAUCAGAAUACAAACCAGUAAGGCAACACGAAUAAACUAAGAAAAAGGUAAGAACUGUCUCAAAAACGAAAGCACACCACCCAAGACACAGUACCCAGUCAUGGUUUCCCCAUCCAACUAUUAGUUUCAUACUUUGAAAACUUACUUUCAGAUUAUUCUCAAAGAACACAGUAGCACCUAAAUCUGUUUUCAAUUGGGCUUAAAAAUUGACAUGCAAUCUCUUAAGUUUUUUGUUCAGCUACUUCACACUGAGUACCUCAAAUCUGCUCUGGAGUCGAUUAUGCCACCUGUGUGUCAGGAUGCACCUGAAAGCCCUCGGCUCGGUCCUUAGACCAUCUUCCUACAUUACCUGGAAGGGAGCUGCCAUCUGUCCCUCUGCAGAGGGAUACCUUCCAAUAGUAAAUUAUCUGGUUCCUCACUGAAACAAGUUAUUUUUGCUUCAUAUAGUCAGAGUCAGACUGACAUGAUAAAAUAUCAUGUUCCUAAUCUGUUGUCUCAGAUAAGUGACCAAGACGGGACUUUCCACAUUUUAGUCUACAUUCUAAUCUUAAAGGAAUAAAGCACUGAAUUGGGACUAACAUUCUGAUAGGUUGCACCCUUAAGAGUAUUCAGAGAGCAUCAAAAGGAGCCCACACCUUCAGCAGUGAAGGAUUCUAACACAGGGAAUCUGCAGUUUGUAGCAGAAUGGUAUUUUCCUCAAGUAGCUCAUAAUACUGCCAAAUCUCAAAAGUUAAGCUGAAUUUCACACCAGAUCCUACCCCUUUCCCUGAGCCACAUGUUUCACACAAGUGUAGAAAAUGCCAGGGAUCCACCACAAGAUGGAGAUGGUCAGCACAAACCGAUUCUGUUCCUCUUUAAAGUGUAUAUUAGCCACUUAGCAAUCUCUAUAUUCUUUCAAGUAACCAAGCUGUUGACUUUCUUACUACUUGCAGUAGCCUGUCCCCAACUUUUCCAUCCAGUGCUUAACCUAAAAAACUCCUUAACUCUGCCUUGACCUGAGGAAGACCAUGCUAACUGGUGUUAUUUUGUAUGUACCCUGUGCUUAAUUCUAUAACAGUAAACCCCAUACGCAGGUGGGAGGGAGGAACACCGGUGCCUCGGUCACUCUGGGGGCAGUUUAGAUGCUGUGAAAUUAAACCUGUUCUAAGUGUACUUGUUUGAAUUAAUUGUAUUGUAAUAUUAUUUGUUGAAUGUAGUAAUUAGGUAUUUAUGAAUAUAUUGCUGUAAUUUCUGACAACAUCCAAAAAAUAAAAUCUUCCUAAAUUA